CCCAGACCAGCAGAGGCAGCAGCCGGAGCAGCCGCAGCCUGCGCCCUCUCCCGCCCGCCCGCCCUCCGCCCGCCCGCCCGCCCUCCGCCGCCCUCCACCCGCCCCGGGGUCUCUUUCCCCCUUCCUCCUCCUCCUCCUCCACCCCCCCUUCCUCCUCCGCCCGCCCGCGGGGCCCCCCUCGCCUUCCCGCCCGCCCCUAUUGUUCCGCCCCCGGCCUCCCGCCCUUCCCCUUCCCGCCCGCUCCCCUUUUCCCCUCAGUCGCCUCGCGCCUGCAGUUUUUGGCUUUCACCCCCAACCAGUGACCAAAGACUUGACCACUCAAAGUCCAGCUCCCCAGAACACUGCUCGACAUGGACACCGGUGUGAUUGAAGGUGGAUUAAAUGUCACUCUCACCAUCCGGCUACUUAUGCAUGGAAAGGAAGUUGGCAGUAUCAUCGGAAAGAAAGGAGAAUCAGUUAAGAAGAUGCGCGAGGAGAGUGGUGCACGUAUCAACAUCUCAGAAGGGAAUUGUCCUGAGAGAAUUAUCACUUUGGCUGGACCCACUAAUGCCAUCUUCAAAGCCUUUGCUAUGAUCAUUGACAAACUGGAAGAGGACAUAAGCAGCUCUAUGACCAAUAGCACAGCUGCCAGUAGACCCCCGGUCACCCUGAGGCUGGUGGUCCCUGCUAGUCAGUGUGGCUCUCUCAUUGGAAAAGGUGGAUGCAAGAUCAAGGAAAUACGAGAGAGUACAGGGGCUCAGGUCCAGGUGGCAGGGGAUAUGCUACCCAACUCAACUGAGCGGGCCAUCACUAUUGCUGGCAUUCCACAAUCCAUCAUUGAGUGUGUCAAACAGAUCUGCGUGGUCAUGUUGGAGACUCUCUCCCAGUCCCCCCCGAAGGGCGUGACCAUCCCGUACCGGCCCAAGCCGUCCAGCUCUCCGGUCAUCUUUGCAGGUGGUCAGGACAGGUACAGCACAGGCAGCGACAGUGCGAGCUUUCCCCACACCACCCCGUCCAUGUGCCUCAACCCUGACCUGGAGGGACCACCUCUAGAGGCCUAUACCAUUCAAGGACAGUAUGCCAUUCCACAGCCAGAUUUGACCAAGCUGCACCAGUUGGCAAUGCAACAGUCUCAUUUUCCCAUGACGCAUGGCAACACCGGAUUCAGUGGCAUUGAAUCCAGCUCUCCAGAGGUGAAAGGCUAUUGGGCAGGUUUGGAUGCAUCUGCUCAGACUACUUCUCAUGAACUCACCAUUCCAAACGAUUUGAUUGGCUGCAUAAUCGGGCGUCAAGGCGCCAAAAUCAAUGAGAUCCGUCAGAUGUCUGGGGCGCAGAUCAAAAUUGCGAACCCAGUGGAAGGAUCUACUGAUAGGCAGGUUACCAUCACUGGAUCUGCUGCCAGCAUUAGCCUGGCUCAAUAUCUAAUCAAUGUCAGGCUUUCCUCGGAGACGGGUGGCAUGGGGAGCAGCUAGAACAAUGCAGAUUCAUCCAUAAUCCCUUUCUGCUGUUCACCACCACCCAUGAUCCAUCUGUGUAGUUUCUGAACAGUCAGCGAUUCCAGGUUUUAAAUAGUUUGUAAAUUUUCAGUUUCUACACACUUUAUCAUCCACUCGUGAUUUUUUAAUUAAAGCGUUUUAAUUCCUUUCUCUGUUCAGCUGUUGAUGCUGAGAUCCAUAUUUAGUUUUAUAAGCUUCUCCCUGGUUUUUUUUUUUUGGCUCAUGAAUUUUUCUGUUUGUCAUGGAAAUGUAAGAGUGGAAUAUUAAUACAUUUCAGUUUAGUUCUGUAAUGUCAGGAAUUUUUCAAAAAAAUUAAAAGAUGGACUGGAGCUUUUUCUUUGUGAAUAGAAACUGGAUGCCACAGUGAUUCAUGUGGGUUUUAUUCCUCUUGUCUUGCUGUUAUUUUUGUACCUUUUAUCCCUCAAAGGACCCUUCUUGGGUUUUGAAUGGAAGCCUUUAUUCCGGUUAAGAUGUUUUCUUCUAUUUUACCACUUCCAUCUUUUUUUGUGGCCCUCGAUCCUAUUUUUCCCUGACUCCAUGCUUGGUUGGCCCUUAUAAAACUUGUGCCCAAAAGAUUGAGGAUUAGACUUUCCGAGGACUUACCUGUCCUAGGGGAGUAGGCAAGCACUUCCACUAGGGAGGGGGUGGGGGAAAGGAAUGACACAUGACAUACAUGGCAUACACAUUAAGCAGUUGAUCAUAUGUCUGACUGGGUUCCAGUUUCUUGGGAAUGUUGGUCCCCUUGUUCAGGCUUGCAUAUUUUAAACUAAAAAUUUCAGUCUAUUGUUUUUAGUAACUUCAUUUAUAGUCCUCCAUAACAAGUUAGAAGGAUGUAUCUGCUACCAUUUAUUCCUAUAAUUUUAGAAAGUUGGGGCUUGACAUUAUACUCAUUUAGUGAGAGUAGAUGCAAAAAAGUGGAGGGGCAGGAGAACUUCUCCAGACACCUCAGAUAAAGUCCGGAGCCCAAGGCUUUAUCUUAACCAUGUAUGGUACCCCAUUCAUUCAUCAAGAAAACCCUCAACAGCUGGGCCUGCAUGGAGUGUUAUAUUUCAAGGUUUUUCACAGGGGUUACAGUAGGACAGUCCCCACCCCAAUCAGGCACCAGGAUAAAAGCAGGGACUUAAACAGCACCCCGGUUCUUCAGCCUGAGCCAUCACAUGCUAUCAGUCUCCUAACCUCCCCCUGGGCCUUAAGACAGGGCUUGGGCAGAGAAGAUAAAUGGUGGGACAAAAAAAUGAGUUACAUUGCCACCUGAGAAACCUCAGAGGGGAGGACCCAGCCUUAGCCUCCCUCCUCCCAAGUGCAAAAUGUGUAAACAGAGUAAACGGAACAGAAAAGUGCAGUCUAAGUGGUUUUCUCUCCUGCCCCUCCCACCGCCCCUCCCCCCACCCCCUAUUAUUUGGGGAUAAAGAAUAUAAAGACAACCCUGGCUUUUCUAUUGCCUUGUUGCUUGCUGAAUAUAAGGAAUGGGGUGGGGCAGGAAGGGGCUUGCCCUUAGCCACAGCUCUACGGCUGUGCCUCAUUCAUUUCCACAGCUGCCAGUGUCCCUAGAGUUUAUCAGGUGAAUUGGUCAGGGGAUCAGUCUCCCUCGAGCCUGACUUACGGCUGGGACAGCCCCAUCUUUCUGUUGAUUAUGUGGCGCAUAUAUAUAUAUAUAUGUAUAUAUAUAUAAUUUAUAUAAAUAUUUCUCUAUGUA